CAAAUUCAUAAGAAACAAGGAAAAGAACAAAAAAGAAAGGAACUACAUUAACCUUCAAGUAUUCUACACAUCAAGGAAAAAUUUAGUGGCAUACAAAUGUCACCUAAUAAGUGGGUGAAACCUGGGCAUGCUGGCUCAUGCCUAUAAUUCUAGAAAUUUAGGAGGCCAAGUCAGAACGAUCAUUUGAGGCCAAAAGUUUGAGACUAGCCAUGAAAAUAUAUCAAGACCCUGUCUUGUAUAGGGUAAUAUAUGUGCAUACAUACAUACAUAUAACAAAAAAGUGUAAAAAUAUUUUCUAAUCACAUAUUUCGUAGGUGUUAAUUUCCAAAAGAUAUAAACUUCUAAAAUUCAACAACAACAAAAUGUUAAUAACUUGAUUUAGAAUGGUAAAUGUUUGAAAUGACCUUUCUCCAAAGAAGACAUAGAAAUGACUAGGUAUUUAAAAGGAUACUCGUCCGAGGGCAGGACUAUGGGAGGCUGCCCUGUACGGAAAAUAAGAAGAAAUGGCAGUAAAGAGGGCAACCAUCAUUCCACCCAGCCCAAAAGGAAUAAGAGAAACCCUAUCUUUCAGGAUUCUCAAGACACAGUUUUCAUGGAGUGAUAAUGAAAGGAGCAGCAGCCGCCUUAAUAUCCCAGAGAGAGCAGGUGGACCAGAAAGCAACUUAAACCAGAUUGUUACUGAACCCAAUGCAAACUUUCCCCAGUUCUUGCAUGAGGGGUAUGUACCAUGCCAAGGUCUUUACUCCCAUAUCAACCAGACCUUGAAGGAGGCUCACUUCAACAGCCUGCAGCAGUGAGGGCAAGCUCCAACAUGAUGAAUUAGGACUUCCUUAUUCCAACCUAAACUGUGUUUAUAAAAGUAAUUGCAUACAAACUAAAAAAAAAGUCUAUUGGUUUUUAAGUCUAAAUUUUAAGUAACAAGUUAAUGGGCAGUAGUUUAAUUGGGGUUUUACUUCACUGCUAUACUUUUAAAGGGGCUGUGAAUAAAUGUUUAUGAAAUUAAAAAAAUAAAAAAUAAAAGGAUACUCGACAUCACUCUUCUAGAAAAAUGCAAAGCAAAGUCACAAUAAUCUACGGCCUCAAGCCGAUAUUUAAAAUAGUAUGACAGCUCUUCAAAAAAUUUAAAAUGAGAUUAUUAUAUAAUCCAGCAAACCCCCUUCUGGCUAUGUACUUAAAAUGUACAACGCAGAUCUGGAAGAGAUAUUUGCACAACCAAAUUUAUUGCAAUAUUAUUAACACAAGCCAAAAGGCAGAAACAAUCCAGAUGUCCCUUGACCAAUGAACAGAUUAAUAACAAGUGGCACAUACACAAAGUCGAAUAUUAUUCAGUCUUUAAAAAGACACAUUAUAUGAUAAUUCUGGAGAAGAUCAUGUUAAUUGAAAUAAGCCAGGAACAAAGUGACAGUCUAUGAUUCCAUUCAUAAUCAGGUAUCUUAAGUAGAUAAACUCAUAGGAAAAAAAAGUUAGAAUGGUGCUUGUCAAGGACUGAAGAGAUGGUAAAAUGGGCAGUUGUUUUAUUUUUUAUUUUUUUAUUUUUUUUAUUUUUUUAAAUUAUACUUUAAGUUUUAGGGUACAUGUGCACAUUGUGCAGGUUAGUUACAUAUGUAUACAUGUGCCAUGCUGGUGUGCUGCACUCACUAACUCGUCGUCUAGCAUUAGUUGUAUUUCCCAAUGCUAUCCCUCCCCCCUCCCCCCACCCCACAACAGUCCCCAGAGUGUGAUAUU